AGACGCCUGAGUCGGAGAGACAGGGGGCAGAGGUUGCCAAGCCCUGGCUGCCACUUGUCAGGUUCCCUGUGCUAGACAUGCAUAAUCUGUAUUCCAUCACUGGGUACCCGGACCCACCAGGGACCAUGGAGGAGGAGGAGGAGGAUGAUGACUAUGAGAACUCAACACCUCCCUACAAGGACCUUCCUCCCAAGCCAGAUGCCCAGUCAUCCCUUUGGAGAGGCUCACAUGGCAAGGAACUGAGGCCUCCCACCAACAGCCAUGUGAGUGCAUCAUCUUGGAAGCAGAUCCUCUAGCCCCAGUCAAGCCUGCAGAUGACUUGCAGUCCCAGGCAACAUCUUGACUACAAUCACGCAAGAGAUCUCAAGCUAGAACUACCCAGCUAAGCUGCUCUCAGAUUCCUGAACCACAGAAACUGGACCAUGGAGGAGGAGGAGGAGGAUGAUGACUAUGAGAACUCAACACCUCCCUACAAGGACCUUCCUCCCAAGCCAGUCUCUUCCCACAACGACUCAGAGCUGGUCCAUGUGAUAAAUAGAAUACUGUAUAGUGGAGACCAUCCUUUGUGACUUGUGAGGCUAGAUCAUAGGAGCAUGGUGGCUUCUAUCUUUGCCUCUGCCAUGUUGUGAAGAUGCCCAGUCAUCCCUUUGGAGAGGCUCACAUGGCAAGGAACUGAGGCCUCCCACCAACAGCCAUGUGAGUGCAUCAUCUUGGAAGCAGAUCCUCUAGCCCCAGUCAAGCCUGCAGAUGACUUGCAGUCCCAGGCAACAUCUUGACUACAAUCACGCAAGAGAUCUCAAGCUAGAACUACCCAGCUAAGCUGCUCUCAGAUUCCUGAACCACAGAAACUGGACCAUGGAGGAGGAGGAGGAGGAUGAUGACUAUGAGAACUCAACACCUCCCUACAAGGACCUUCCUCCCAAGCCAGGUUCAAGUGCUCCACCAAGACCUCCAAGGGCAGCAAAGGAAACAGAGAAACCCCCACUUCCUUGCAAGCCCCGGAACAUGACAGGCCUGGACCUCGCCGCUGUCACCUGUCCACCUCCUCAACUGGCUGUGAAUCUUGAGCCUUCUCCAUUGCAGCCAUCCCUGGCCGCAACUCCAGUCCCCUGGCUCAAUCAGAGGUCUGGAGGUCCUGGCUGCUGCCAGAAGAGGUGGAUGGUGUACCUGUGUCUGCUGGUGGUGACUUCCCUGUUCCUGGGCUGCCUUGGUCUCACUGUGACCCUGAUUAAGUACCAGGAGUUGAUGGAAGAACUGAGAAUGUUAAGCUUUCAGCAGAUGACGUGGCGAACAAAUAUGACUGGCAUGGCAGGGCUAGCUGGCCUGAAGCAUGACAUUGCCCGUGUAAGAGCUGACACCAACCAGUCCCUGGUGGAACUUUGGGGCUUAUUAGACUGCCGCCGAAUUACCUGUCCUGAAGGCUGGCUGCCCUUUGAGGGCAAGUGUUACUACUUCUCCCCAAGCACCAAGUCAUGGGAUGAGGCCCGGAUGUUCUGCCAGGAGAAUUACUCUCACUUGGUCAUCAUCAAUAGCUUUGCUGAGCACAAUUUUGUGGCCAAGGCCCAUGGCUCUCCACGGGUGUACUGGCUGGGGCUGAAUGACAGGGCCCAGGAAGGGGACUGGAGGUGGCUGGAUGGGUCUCCUGUGACAUUAAGCUUCUGGGAGCCAGAGGAACCCAAUAACAUCCACGAUGAGGACUGUGCUACCAUGAACAAAGGUGGCACCUGGAAUGAUCUCUCUUGCUACAAAACUACGUAUUGGAUUUGUGAGCGGAAAUGUUCCUGUUGAAGCCCAGGGCCGAGGCUGGGGGUCCAUAUCUGAGUGUCUCUUUGAGAUGAGAAUCUCCUGCCCUUUCGUGGACGGCCUUGCCUCUUCGUGAGUGGACACACAGAUGUGCCUCAAACAGGAUUGGCACCCUGGAUGCAGCAAGUUCCCAGGGGUGCAAGUCAGGCUGUUUCUAGAGUGAGGACUUGGGCUUGCCCUAGUAGAUGGUGAGCUGGGAGGAUGCUCAGAGCUUGGUGGUGGGAGGUCUCCCACUUCUGGGGUUGAAAGGAUCUUCACUAAGUUCCUGAUCAUGACUCUUGGGAAGUGAUACUAGCCCUGAGGACCCUGGGGCUGGUGUUGAACCUGGGAUGAAAUAUCCUGGCGCCUGUGAACCACAAAGAGCUGGGACUGGGCUCCUUUUCCUGCAGCCUCAAACUUCUGGGCUCAGGUGAUCCUCCCAUCUCAGCCUCCUGAGUAGCUGGGACUACACAUGCGCACCACCAUGCCUGGCCAAUUUUUUGUAGCAUUUAAAGAGAGGGAGUCUCACUAUGUUGCCCAGGCCAGUCUCAAACUCCUUGCCUCAAUGGAUCCUCCUACUUGGGCUUCCCAAAUUGUGAGGAUUACAGGUGUGAGCCACUGUGCCUGGCUCAAAAUUAUUAUUAUUAUUUUUAUAGAGAUGAGGUCUCACUCUGUUGCCGAGGCUGGUCUCAAACUCCUGGGGUCAAGCAAUCCUUCCGUGAUGGCCUCCCAAAGUGCUGGGAUUACAGGCAUGUGUCACCGUACCUGGCCGAUAUUUUUAUUUUUAUUUUUACUUUCCCCAUCUUUUCCUUUUUUUUUUUUUUCCAAACAAAAGCUUUGAAAGUGGUGACAGAAAAAUUUCCCUUUGAGCUAGACCUCUAGAUCUGCCUCGCACAGAAAUACAUUAAGUGGGCUGGUCUCAUGUAGUCCCCACAUCAUUGCAAAUUACAAACCUAAAAAUACAGAACAUCAGCGGAGAAGACAGGAGAGCUUCUAUAUUCACCCCAUGUCGUCCUCUCCAGACACUGCUUCCUUCCUGGUCUCAAACAGCACAAAUAACCCAGAAACCAUCAAAAUUAUUUUUGACCAGCAACUUUCUCAAUGUCUUGGGUGAGGUUUGCACAAGCUAAGUGGCAGAAUCAGACUUUUGCCAGAAGACUUGGCCCGUGGAACUUCUAUCCUUUUUUUUUUUUUUUUUUUUUUUUGAGAUAGGGUUUCAUUCUACUACCCAGGCUGGAGUGCAGUGGCACAAUCAUAGCUUACUGCACCCUCUGCCUCCUGGGCUCGAGUGAUCCUCCUGCCUCAGCCUCCCAAGUAGCUGGGACUACAGGCGUUCACCCUCACACCUGGCUGGCCCAUGGAACUUCUAGAAAGGCAUACCAGCUGAAAAGCAAGACCCCUACAUAGUGUGGCCAGGCAGGCCAUAACCUGGUCAUAUCCACACAGGACAACGAUGGACCUAUCUGCCAGCACGUGCCCUUGAGCUAUCUGUGGGUUGUAACGUCUUUGAUGAUAUAAUUCACUUUACUUGCCAGGCACAGUGGCUCACGCCUGUAAUCCCAGCACUCUGGGAGACUGAGGUGGGCUGAUCACCUGGGGUCAGG